UGGUGUGGCUGCUUGGUGCAGCCCACACCUGGUCAGCUCCCACCUGUGGAGAAACUCCAAACUAGAGCCUCCUACUGGGAUGAAGCAGAAGCAGAUGCCUGGAGUCCCAGAAUGACUGGACUACCCUUUUAGCUGCAUUCUGCAUCCCAUCAUUCCAGACGGUGUUACAUGCAGCCCUCAGCUACCUCCUACAGACGUGAUCGGCUCCUGUCCUCUCAAGGUUUCUCCCUCCCUCCCUUCCUUCCUCCCUCCAUUCCUCCCUCCCUCGUUUCUUCCUAUCUCACUCUCCUUCUUUCCUCCCUCACUCUCCUUCCUUCCUUCCUGCCUCCCUCCCUCCCUUUCUUCCUUCCUUCCUCACUCUCCUUCUUUCCUCCCUCACUCUCCUUCCUUCCUGCCUCCCUCCCUCCUUUCUUCCUUCCUCACUCUCCUCCUUUCCUCCCUCACUCUCCUUCCUUCCUUCCUUCGUUCCUUCCUUCCUCCUUCCCUCCCUCCCUCCUUCCUUCCUCCUGCAGUCCCCAUCCUUCCUUCCUUUUAUCCUUCUUUCCUUCCUCCCUCCCUCCCUCUCUUUCUUCCUCCCUUUUUUCUUUCUUUUCCUCCUCCUCCUCCUCCUCCUUUUCUCUCUCUCUCUCUCCCCCCACCUUGUUCACUCACUCGCUGUCGAUUCUUGUGAUCUGAAUUGAUAUGAACAAGAGUGUGUAGACGGUCAGUCAUGGGGAAGCAGCAUCUCCUAGUGGCCUUUGAAACAGCCACCAGCAACUGAGACUCGCUCUGUCGCCAGGGUGGAGUCCAGUGGCGCCAUCUCGGCUUACUGCAACCUCCGCCUCCCAGGUUCAAGAGAUUCUCCUGUCUCUGCCUCCCGAAGAGCUGGGACUACAGGCACAGCCUCCAUGCAGAGAGCCAAUCACUCCACAGUGACCCAAUUCAUCCUCGUCGGCUUCUCUGUCUUCCCCCACCUCCAGCUGAUGCUCUUCCUGCUGUUCCUGCUGAUGUACCUGUUCACGCUGCUGGGCAACCUGCUCAUCAUGGCCACCGUCUGGAGCGAGCGCAGCCUCCACACGCCCAUGUACCUCUUCCUGUGCGCCCUCUCCGUCUCCGAGAUCCUCUACACCGUGGCCAUCAUCCCGCGCAUGCUGGCCGACCUGCUGUCCACCCAGCGCUCCAUCGCCUUCCUGGCCUGUGCCAGUCAGAUGUUCUUCUCCUUCAGCUUCGGCUUCACCCACUCCUUCCUGCUCACCGUCAUGGGCUACGACCGCUACGUGGCCAUCUGCCACCCCCUGCGCUACAACGUGCUCAUGAGCCCGCGGGGCUGCGCCUGCCUGGUGGGCUGCUCCUGGGCUGGUGGCUUGGUCAUGGGGAUGGUGGUGACCUCGGCCAUUUUCCACCUCGCCUUCUGUGGACACAAGGAGAUCCACCAUUUUGCUUGCCAUGUGCCACCUCUGUUGAAGUUGGCCUGUGGAGACGAUGUGCUGGUGGUGGCCAAAGGCGUGGGCUUGGUGUGUAUCACGGCCCUGCUGGGCUGUUUUCUCCUCAUCCUCCUCUCCUAUGCCUUCAUCGUGGCCGCCAUCUUGAAGAUCCCUUCUGCUGAAGGUCGGAACAAGGCCUUCUCCACCUGUGCCUCUCACCUCACUGUGGUGGUCGUGCACUAUGGCUUUGCCUCCGUCAUUUACCUGAAGCCCAAAAGUCCCCAGUCUCUGGAAGGAGACACCUUGAUGGGCAUCACCUACACGGUCCUCACACCCUUCCUCAGCCCCAUCAUCUUCAGCCUCAGGAACAAGGAGCUGAAGGUCGCCAUGAAGAAGACCUUCUUCAGUAAACUCUACCCAGAAAAAAAUGUAAUGAUGUAGGAGAAAUUCACUGGGAACAACUAAAUUGGAUUACCGAAGGCUAUUGUUAAAAAUUACGUUCCGUGGUGACUCAUGCCUGUAAUCCCAGCACUUUGGGAGGCCGAGGCAGGCGGAUCACCUGAGGUCAGGAGUUUGAGACCAGCAUGGCUAACAUGGCGAAACCCCAUCUCUACUAAAAAUACAAAAAUUAGCCAGGCAUGUUGGCACAUGCCUGUAACCCUAGCUACUUGGGAGGCUGAGGCAUAAGAAUCGCUUGACCCGGUAGGUGGAGGUUGCAGUGAGCUGAGAUCACACCACUGCACUCCAGCCUGGGCGACAGAGUGAGACUGUCUCAAAGAAGAAAGAAAGAAAGAAAAAAAGAAAAUUACGUUCCAGCCAAGCACUGUGGCUCACACUUAUAAUUCCAGCACCUUGGGAUGCCAAGGCAGGAGGAUUGCUUGAGGCCAGGAGUUCAAGACUAGACUUGACAACAUAGCAAGACUGCAUAUCUACAAAAACUUAGAAAAAAAUAGCUUGGCAUGGUGGUACAUGCCUGUAGUCCCAGCUACCUGGGAGACUGAACUGGGAUUACUGCCUAAGUCCAGAAGUUUGAGCUUACAGUGAACUAUGACUGUGCCACUGCAGUCUAGCAUGGAUGACAGAGUGAGACCCUAUCCCUUCCCCCCUAAAAGAAAGACAAUCCAUGAACAUAUAGUAACCUCUAUUUGUCAUGCUUUAAGGUUUACAAGGGACCUUGUAGACGACAUACAAUUAUAAACACAAAGGUUAAUCAGCAUCAGGGAUGUAUUUGGAGUGGAAGUGUGUGUGAGAUACUAACACAGAGAAAACCAGGUUUGAUUAUUUCUAUCUGCUGCAAGAAACUGUGUCAGUUAGCACCAAACCUCCAUCUAGACUCCUCUUGCCAAAAGCCAGGGUCAUCUAAUACCCCCAAUAAUGCAAACCAGCAAUGCAAAGAGAGAGGGAAGAUUUCAUGCCCCACUCUCUAUGAGUGCCGCACCAGGUAGCUACAACUCAGAUUUUGUAAGGCUACUCCAGAUUAUAGCAGAGGAGAGAAAAGUACCCUAAAUUUCAGCAUUGCACAGAUCUAUGCAAUAGAAGUUAGAAAUAGCAAUAAACAGACUCUCUUUAAACAUCAAGGAAACCUUAGAAUUUCAAGUGUGAGUCUUGAAUAGUUGUGGAGAGACUGAGAUGUCUUCAUGGUUGGAUCAAGGAAAAAAGUCACACUGUGAGAUACCGAAUGCUGUGUUAGAAGUUGACACGGCUCAUGGGCCAGCCAGGAGCUCUCUGUUGAAUCUGGACAUUGAGUGUAGACCCCAGGAUGAGUUUAUCUCAUGGCCAGGCGCAGUGGCUCAUGCCUGUAAUCCCAGCACUUUGGGAGGCCAAGGUGGGUGGAUCCCCUGAGGUCAGGAGUUCAAGAGCAGCCUGGGCAAAUGGCUGAAACCCCAUCUCUACUAAAAAUAUAAAAAUUAGCCAGGCGUGGUGGCAGGUGCCUGUAAUCCCAGCUACUCAGGAGGCUGAGACAGGAGAAUAGCUUGAACCAUGGAGGCAGAGGUUGCAGUGAGCUGAGAUCACACCACUGCACUCCAGCCUGGGUGACAGACUGAGACUCCAUCUCAAAAAAAAAAAAAAAAAAAAAAAAGAAAGUUUACCUCAUGGUCUCUUCCCAAUGGGCAGGGAUUUAAGAUUGACCCUACUGUAUAGUAUUUAUAUAUUUAUUGACAAUAGGUCUUCCUGUGUUUGAGCUAUGCAUCAUUUUUUUCUAAAGUGUGAAUUCUCCAUCAUUCAAGCAGUCAAAACAACCCACAGUCAAAACAUCCCAUAUUACAAAAGCCAAAAUUGACAAAUGGGAUCUAAUUAAACUAAAGAGCUUCUGCACAGCAAAAGAAACUACCAUCAGAGUGAACAGGCAACCUACAGAAUGGGAGAAAAUUUUUGCAAUCUACUCAUCUGACAAAGGGCUAAUAUCCAGAAUCUACAAUGAACUCAAACAAAUUUACAAGAAAAAAACAAACAAUCCCAUCAAAAAGUGGGCAAAGGAUAUGAACAGACACUUCUCAAAAGAAGACAUUUAUGCAGCCAAAAAACAUAUGAAAAAAUGCUCGUCAUCACUGGCCAUCAGAGAAAUGCAAAUGGAAACCACAAUGAGAUAUCAUCUCACACCAGUUAGAAUGGCAAUCACUAAAAAGUCAGGAAACAACAGGUGCUGGAGAGGAUGUGGAGAAAUAGGAACACUUUUACACUGUUGGUGGGACUGUAAACUAGUUCCCCAUUGUGGGAGUCAGUGUGGCGAUUCCUCAGGGAUCUAGAACUAGAAAUAUCAUUUGACCCAGCCAUCCCAUUACUGGGUAUAUACCCAAAGGAUUAUAAAUCAUGCUGCUAUAAAGACACAUGCACACAUGUUUACUGCAGCACUAUUCACAGUAGCAAAGACUUGGAACCAACCCAAAUGUCCAACAAUGAUAGACUGGAUUAAGAAAAUGUGGCACAUAUACACCAUGGAAUACUAUGCAGCCAUAAAAAAUGAUGAGUUCA